AUUAACCUCCCGGGAGCCCAAGCAUGUCAGGAUUGCCACCGCACCGUCCGACCGCUGGUGGAAGGCACUGGCAUUGUCAGAGCUGGAACAUCCCGGGGCUGCGGGGGUAGGCGGUGUGAAGCGAAUUAUGUAAAGAGGAUUUACAAACCGAACUUUAGGAAACUUCAGAGGAAUGGGCAUGUCCAAAAUGUUGGAUGUGAUGUGAUACUUUGGCCUGGUUGUGCACAUUCAUUGUAAUUCCCCCCAGUGAUUCUUGGCUGGCAGCAGUUGAGUCUCUACUACCUUUUGCAUUGUAAAUGAGGUACUGAUAACGUUGGCAGCCCUUCAAGUGACUUACUUUUCUUGGAUGUUAAUAAUAUCCAUGCUAAUUUCUUUUUUGCUGACUAAUGUAGCAGCUUUUGCCCUUUUCCUGCUUAAUACUGAGCAGAUCCAAGGAAAUGCAUACACAGGCUAGAUCACUGUAAUUAUUGUAAAUAUUUAAAAACGGUAAAACCUCAGUUUUUAGAACCUUUGGAAAGUUAGUUAUGAAAGCUGUGGAUUUAUCCCUUUAAGCACCAAACCCAUUUUUUAAUAACCCGUUUCAUUUUUGUAGUCCUUUCAGACAGUAUUCUUUCAUAGGAAGUCUUUUGAUCUUAACAGCAGAGCAGUCCUGUAAGGUGAGGAGGAUUGCUGGGAUUAUCCAACAUCAUUUACAGAUCAGUACACUGAAGCUCAGAAAGAUUUGCUCAAGGUCACAGAAGUUGGACUAUUCUAAGAAUUUUAACUCUAAAAGCGAUGUCUUAGUUGAGUGAAGUACUUAGGGAUGUUCUACACAAACUCUGCUGUCUGUCGCCUUCCCCCCAUUUUUUUUUCUUUCUUUUUUGAGACGGAGUCUUGCUCUGUCGCCCAGGCUGGAGUGCAGUGGCGCGAUCUCAGCUCACUGCAACCUUCGCCUCCCAGGUUCAAGUGAUUCUCCUGCCUCAGCGCCCCGAGUAGCUGGGAUUACAGGUGCCUGCCACCAUGCCCGGCUAAUGUUUGUAUUAUUUAGUAGAGACAGGGUUUUGCCAUGUUGGCCAGGCUGGUCUCCAACUCCUGACCUCAGGUGAUUCCCCCUGCCUUGGCCUUCCAAAAUGCUGGGAUUACAGGCGUGAGCCAUGGCGCCCAGCCCUUCCUCCCAUUUUUGCUACCCACCUGUCACUUCUUGACAUUGUGAUUAUUUAUGUCAUACUGUUUCUGAUCUGUUCUGGGCCUGGGAAUCAAAUAGCCAUGUUUGCUAGGCCUUUGUAUGAGAUGCUGCAUUUUGACUGAGGCCUCAGGACUCCCGGGUGAAAGGUGGGUAUAUACAAAAGUGACAUUGCGUGGUUUGACACCUUUUGAUUCCUUCCUGCUUUUUCUUUAUUGCAUAAUUGAUACAUUGCUUGAAUGCUAGAUUCCCCCCAUCUACCCCCACAUCUCAUUUAACAAAGAAGUAUAGAAACAUCCUGGGGAGACAGUGUGGAGUGGACCUGGGAGUCUAGCAUAUGUGAGUUCUAGUCCCCGUUCUGCCACUUCCUGCCUUCUGUGAUGCUGGGCUAGCUACUUGACAUCUCUCUCCUAGCUUCUGUUCUGUAGAAUGGGGGAAAACAAUAGUUGCCACCCCCAGACACCAUGUUGUGGAGAUGUGUCUGGCUUAUACUCAACUCAGUGACUGUAUUGUAGCUAUUAGCUCUUAGUAACAGAAAAUUAGUUUUUAGUAUUAUAUUUCUAAGAUUUGUAUGUCCCUGCCUCUUUAAGUAUUUGGUUUGUAUUAAUACCUUUUGGUCUUGUUAUAUAAUAUUCUAGCUGUAAAAGCAUUUCAUCAAUGAAUUGAGGAAGUCUCUGAUUUUAAAUACUUUAAUCAGUAAAAUUUCAGAGAAAAAUCUUUAAGACAUUUGAUUGGUAAGAUGAUAAUACAUGGCAGAACACACAAGCUUACUUUUUUUAAUAGGCAAGAAGAUGUGUGAAAACAGCCUUAAAAAAAAAAAGCCUAAGAAUUCCAGUCUUUCAGCCUGGAAUAUGAACAAAGUUUCUUUAAUAACAAAGAAAAAAAUGACACCAAAUGAUCAAUAACUUAGAGUUUACAAAAACUAUCAGAGAGUAAAAGGGCCAGGGAAAAUGCAGACACUGGUAGGGAUGGUUCGGUGGAGGAUGGAAACACUCAUAAAAUAAUGGGCCCUACAGGUAUUCUACAGGUUGAACCAGGCCCUUGAAUGCAUCUUGGGAACCAAAAUGAAAAGUGAAACAACUCUGUGCCUCGUAAACCAUGAAAAAACAUAACAGGUACUCAAGGGAAGCACAGUAUUUCCUGGCAAAAUGUUGGAGUUGGGGGUAGUUUCCCGUAAAGUUGGAUGGGAAGAGAGGACGCAGUGAAGCAUGUCUUCAUCAGGUUUAGAGCAAAUGCCGCAGGAACCUUUCUUACAGGUCUCAGGGAAAGUGGAAAAAAUAAAUUGACAAAUGGGGAGCUGAAAUAAUCUUACCUCGGUAUGUUUUUUUGGGAGGAAGCUAACUGGAAUAUUAAGAAGCAUGGAAUUGGAAUGCACAUUCUUCCAGUCUUCUGCCCCCUUGGAAUGUCUGAUUUGAGCAAAGCAGCUUCCCACGGGAUCUUCUUGAUUACAAAAUGGUUGGUCUUGAACUUCUGGCCUCAAGUGAUCCUACUGCCUUGGCCUGUUAAAGCACUGGGAUUACAGGUGUGAGCCACCAUUCCUAGCCUUGUUUUUCUUAAGUAGUUAAAUAGUUAAUAUUAUGUUGAAAUUUUUCAUCUUUGCUGCUGAUUUUGGGAUUAUUUCUUAAGAUAGAUAUUUUGACUGGGCUCUUUCUUAGACUUCCAAGUUAGGAAUGGUAGAGGUGUCCUCUGCAAGGAUUUGUCCAGUGCCUGCAUUUUCCUGAAUACUGCUGGAGAAGGGGCCAUUCAGCCAGGGACUUUGCUCCUGGUAGGAACCAGCUAUUGCUGUUGGUCUGCUUUAGUUUUUGUUUUCCUGUCUUGACCAAAACAGAUAAAUAAGAUACACUUUGCUGAAGUGACAAGAGAUACCAUGCUUCCUCUUUAAAAUUCUCAUCCUUAUUUACUCUGGAGUUUUAACGAGGAUUAUCGUCAGGCUCACUGAUUUUUUACAGUCUAACAUUUGUGGAAAUUGUUCUGUCUCUAGACAGUCCUUUAGAUUUCAGAAACAAUCUUGACAAUGAUGACAUCGCUAAUACCCACCAUCAACAGAGGUAUAGGCUUUUUUUUUCCCCAGUGCCUGUUUCCCUUCCAGGUUGGGACAUGAGGGUUAGUGUUUCCUGCCUCCUUUCCCUCUUUAACAGUGUAUCCUUAAAGUCAUAAUGAAUCUGAUCUGCGGCAUAAAAAAAGUAAGCACAAUUGGAUCGUUUUGGUUUUUCACCCAUCAUUAGCAUUGUAUUCAGGAGAGUGAGGAAAUGCAUUUUCUUCUCUCUCUUUUUUAUUUUUUUGAGAUGGAGUCUCCCUCUGUUGCCCAGGCUGGAGUGAGGUCGUACGAUCUCGGCUCACUGCAACCUCCACCUCCCAGGUUCAAGCAAUUCUCCUGGCUUAGCCUCCCGAGUAGCUGGAAUUACAGGCACCUGCCACCACAUCUGACUAAUUUUUGUAUUCUUAGUAGAGUUGGAGUUUCACCAUGUUGGCCAGGCUGGUCUCAAACGCCUGACCUCAAGUGAUAACACCUGCCUUGGCCUCCCAAAGAGCUGGGAUUACAGGUGUGAGCAACUGUGCCCAGCCCUGCAUUUUCUUUCUCAGUGAAACUAGGUGGUGGUUGGAGAAAGCUUGUCCUUAGAAUUUGUUGGCAAGUUCCAUUUAAAUCUAGGCAUUACCCUCCUGUAGCAUAUACCAUGUGCAUUGGCUCUCCUUAACUCUGAACUUAUUUUAUAGCCCAAAUGGGCUCUUAACUUAUUUAUGUGUACUUGUACCCUCAGAUUUUUGUUAAGGAUUCUUGGAACUCAUAGGUAGAUCCAGGUUGUUUGUGGGGACGAAGUUUAUACAAUUUGGGGGUCCUCAUUAUGAAAAAUAUAUAAAUAUCUUUUAAGUUUUACAAAAACCUAUGGCCAUGUGAACCCUUUUGAACUUGAAGACUUCUCCAUACCUGUCAUACAAGGUUCUUGUCAGGGAAAGUAGAGCUUAGUGGUUAAGAACAUGGACUGUGGGAACUGGGUUGGAUUCCUGGUUCUGCAUCUUACUGUGAACUUUGGCAAGUGACUUAACCUGCCUGUCUUGUAUGUAAAAUGAGGAUAUCAUAACACUCAUCUUUAUAGGGUUGUUGGGAGAAAUCAGAUAGAUAAUCCAUGUAAAGUGUUUAGAAUAAUGCCUGGAAUCAAAAGCCCACAUUAUAUAAAUUUUAGCCAUGGUUUCAUUUUGCUGACUGGUUCUCUGCUAAUUAGGCUCAGUCUUGUGUUCUGAGCUGCUUUUUCUCUUCUGGAUGUUGAUAUUAUCUCUAGAACUUUAAUAUUCAUUCACGAAUCUGUUUGUAUCUGCCUGAGAUUUCUGGUGGAUAGGGGACAUGACACCAAGCAGUACUACUGUGUUUCAUUUCUGUGUCAGGAAUGUGAUCUGCCCCAGAGUCCUUAUCCAGGACUCCACCACCAGGCAGCGUGUGAGGCAUUUCCACAGUGAAAGCACCAGGUCUGUAGAUCUGCACCAUUCUGUCCACAUUGCCCUUAGGGCUGAGGACUUCUCUGUAGAGCUAGAGGUCUUGCUUACCGGGCUUGGUUGUAUUCUGCUUUUUCUAACAGGUUGAUUCCUUUUAAAUAAGAUAUAUCUUUCCUUUCUUGGUUUCAGAUAGGGCUUGUAUUCCUCCACAGCUAGCUGGUUAACAUAUUUUCCUUCAAGUGUUUGAAUUUGGCUUGCUUGAAUCUGGAGGCUUUGAGUUUAUGUGUUCUUAUGAAGUCUCUACCUAGACCUGUGUGAAGCAAGUCCUUGAGUGGAGAAGACUAAUGCUUAGUUUUCCCCCACAAGGUAGGGAGGGACCAGGAAGCUUCAGGGUGUGGGCGUGACUGUUGAGUGCUGUGUCUGCGGUGGGAAGGCCAGGGAAUUGGAGGCAUGAAUGCAGAGAAAAGAGGAGGCCUUUUGUGCUUGGAAGGACUCUUCUGGGUCAGUUGUAACCUAAGCAUUUAUGGUUAUUUCCCCUCUGCUGGAUAAUUUUCCAGGGAACUCUAGCUGUGGAGUGGCCACACUGGGCGGGCUAUGGCUUCAUUGCUUCUUCCCGCCUCCACUCCCAAAUGUUUGGACACUGAUCUUUCUCCAUUAUCUGCAGCUUCUCACCCUUAAUGUUACCCAGGCUCUGUGAAUGGAUAGAGUGUGCUUCAUUAGUGCACAAUUUCCUGGUCUCCUUUUGUUUCUUGUGGGAGGAAAUAGGAGAGAAAACAAUCAAUACCAUGUGUAGCAAGUCUCUGUCCUGCUGUUGGUUAAUUCAAACAUGUGAUUCCACUUUGAAUGCAAAAAUAGCAACAGCAAUCAUAUUCUGCUUCUAAUUGAGUGUAGAAAUUAUAUGUACAUUAGGCAUCAUCUUGUGAGCUUGCUGUGGUCUUUGGGCCUUAGCAGCUGAGCUGGAACCCUAGGGCUGCUCUUUAGAGUCCACCUAUGGCUAGAUGCCUUCCCCUGAAUGGUUCCAUUCUCUACUCUGAAUACUGGGGUGGAUUUUCCUUAUCUUUCUUCAAAGAAUUGGAUGUUGUAUUUUUUAAAAACCCCAUCCCUACCUCUCCUUGCUUACAUACAGACGCAUUAUUUGCCAGCCAGAUUUUCAUUUCAAGGUUUAUUCAUCUCUGAGCUUCCCCCCCUUCUUUUUCUUCUUUAGUGACACCCUUUCCUGCAGUUGGUCUUACAUCACCUUCAAAAAACAUGCAUGUGGCAGGAGGUUGGUCUUCAUAUGGGCCAGUGGGAGAGUUAAAGUGUUUUUAGUCUGAAACAGCUCUGCCAAAUAUCUUAUGAACUUUUUUUUUUUUUUUUUGAGACAGUCUUGCUCUGUCACCUGGGCUGGAGUACAGUGGCACGAUCUUGGCUCACUGCAACUCUACCUCCUGGGUUCAAGCAAUUCUCACACCUCAGCCUCCUGAGAAGCUGGGAUUACAGUCGCGCACCACCAUGCCCAGCUAAUUUUUGUAUUUUUUGUAGAGAUGGGGUUUUACCAUGUUGGCCAGGAUGGUUUUGAACUCCUGACCUUAAGUGAUCCACCCGUCUCAGCUUCCCAAAGUGUUGGGAUUACAGGUGUGAGCCACCGCACCCAGCCUUAUGAACUUUUGAACUGUGCUGGCAAUGCGCUUUGGAACUAAGGAUUCCUAUGGGCUUGUUUAAAUCAAUUCCUCCCACCCCUUGCCGACUUUUUUUUUUUUUAUUUUAUUUUUUUUGGGAGACAGUCUCACUUUGUCGCCCAGGCUGGAAUACCGUGGUGUGAUCUCGGCUCGUUGUAACCUCUGCCUCUCGGGUUCGAGUGAUUCUCCUGCCUCAGCCUCCUGAAUAGCUGGGACUACAGGCCUAUGCCACCAUGUCUGGCUAAUUUUUUGUAUUUUUAGUACAGUCGGGGUUUCACUAUGUUGGCCAGGCUGGUCUUGAACUUCUGACCUCAGGUGAUCUGUCUGCCUCAGCCUCCCAAAAUGCUGGGAUUACAGGCAUGAGCCACUGUGCCCGGCCCAAUUAGUCCUUUCUACAACUGGGCAAUAUAUUCAUGUGCAUUAGUCUGAUACGAUGAUAUUGGUGGUGGGUACAUUUGGAUAUAUUGUCACAUCUCCAUGAGUUAAAAGGACUUUAUGUUAAGCCAGAGUCUAAGCAUCUUCAGGCAGAUAGCAUAGUUGCCUGUGCUAAGACUGUGUAUAGUACAGAGAGUUCCUGUCUCUCAGCUUUGUUGUAGAGUAGGGAUAGGGGAGCAUCCAAUGAUGGAAAAGACUUAGACUUGGAGUCAGAUCUGGGUCCGAAUCCCUGCUGAGCCCACAACCUUUGGACAAGUCAUCUCUGCAUGAAGACAGUACAUCUACCUCAGGGUGCCAUCUUCCUUGCUUAUGAGAACCACUUCUCUUUAUGCCAACAGUUCCAAAAUAGAAAAGUAAAUAAGUGAAAGUAUCCUGUAUACCUUACUCCUACCCUAAGUGCUUGUACUGCUUUGAAUAUUGUUCAACCAUUUUGAAAACUGAAUUAUAGUCUGUUGUAUGGAUUUCCACUGAUUAUUCACUGCUUCCCUGCUGGUGGAUAUUUCCUUUAAAAGUACUUGUGUAGAAAAGUGUGUAACUUUUGACAUAACAUUUAAAUGUAUUUUGAUAUUGCCAAAUUGCUCUCCAAAAAAAUUAGUUCCUACCAAUGGUAAGAAAGAGGAGGAGGAUCUUUUGAUGUUAAAAAAAGAAAAAAGUAACUUGUUUUAGUUUCUUUAUUACCAAGUCAUGAGUCAUUGACAUCUGUAAUCCCUACUCCAUCCCUCGUCCCCAGCAGACUCAGGUGGGAAUUGACAGUGGGCUGGGAUGAGGGCGUUUUUUCCACAAAUUAUUUGAUAAUAGUUUUUUAAACAGGAAGCUUGGCCAGGCACAGUGGCUCACGCCUGUAAUCCUAACACUUUUUGGGAUGCUGAGGUGGGCGGAUCAACUGAGGUCGGGAGUUCGAGACCAGCCUGACCAACAUGGAGAAAACCCAUCUCUACUAAAAAUACAAAAUUAGCCAGGCAUGGUGGCGCAUGCCUGUAAUCCCAGCUCCUCAGGAGACUGAGGCAGGAGAAUCACUUGAACCUGGGAGGCAGAGGCUGCGGUGAGCCAAGAUCGCGCCAUUGCAAUCCAGCCUGUGCAACAAGAGCGAAAUUCCAUCUCAAAAACAAACAAACAAACAAAAAAUCCAGGAAGCUUUAGGUAGCUUUAAAAUGAUAUCUUAUCAAAAUGGCUAUCAAAUCAUGUCAAGUAAGUGGUUUUUAAUGAUAUAUUGAAUUCAAAGGAAGAAAUCUUUCCAGUAUCUUGAUUGGAAUGGCCAGCAAAGCAUAGAUGGAAGGAUAAGUGUUGACAUUUAUUGAGUUCUUACAACUUAUGUGAAUUAACUCAUUGAUUCUUCCCAGUAACCUUCUGAUGUAAGUGCUGUUAAUGAUCUCUGGUUGGCAGGGAAGAAAACUGAAGCAGAGGAAACUUUGUGCAUGGUGGAAAUGGGCUUCUAAUUCAAGCAUUCAGUUUCCAGAGCCCUUGCUCCUAACCAUUUUAAUCUGAGGCCAGAGCUCAGGGAGAAUUGACAUCUUUCAAGACGAGAGGGUACUGAGUCCAGAGAGGGCAGACCAGAGCAAGAAAUCCCAGGAUAAAGUCCUUUAACAAGAAGCUGGAGGAGGAGAGAUUAGAGGGCCCUCCUGGAAAAUACUAGGUGCUACAGAGAGGCCCAGAGGAUGACUGGAGACAGGCCACUGGAUUUGGCUACUGAGAAGUCACUGAUGACCUGUUUUGUUUGAGACAGGAUCGUCCUCUGUUCCCCACUCCCUGCAAUCCCCCUCCCCUGUUUCCCCCCAGGCUGGAGUGCAGUGGCAUGAUCUUGGCUCACUGCAGCCUUGACCUCCUGGGCUCAAGCAAUCCUCCUGCCUCAGCCUCCCGAGUAGCUGGGACUACAGGUGUGCACCACCAUGCCUGGCUAAUUUUUUGUAUUUUUCGUAGAGACAGGGUUUUACCGUGUUGCCCAGGCUGCACUGGUGACCUUUUGAGAGAUCGUCGGUAGAGCAAAUUUCCAGGGGUUAGGAGAGAGUACUAAGGGAGGAAAUGGGCAGGCUUGGCAUGAAAUAAAUGACAAACAGGACAGUGUAUGAGGCUGGCAGCAGGUUCAAUUAAAAAUUUGCCAUUUCAGGGAAGACAGGGUAGCCUGUGCCCAUUGAUGGACCAAGUAAAGGCAACAGCCCAAAACAGAUGGUGUGUGGGGGCAAAGCAGAAGGGCAGGAGGGUCAGUGGGAAGAGAAGGGGCCCAGCUCAGAAGGGGAAGGGAAGAGGACCAUGAAAACGCAGCACUGAUGUGGAGAAGUCCUCUUUUCAUCUGAAAUAGGGGUGUCACUUUGCUCCUGACCUUAUUAUGCUAGAGCCACUGAUGUCCGAUGGGGAAGAGAGCAGGAAUAGGAAGAGAUGGCCCAGGCUAAGCCCUCCCUGUGAGCGCACUGCUGAUUGGGCUGCCCCUUUGGAGCUUGGGCACUGGUUCACUCUCCUCUUUCCAUUGGCCCUUGAUCUGGAAGGGAUGGGAAGUUGGGUUUAUUUUGUUAGAGCCUGGUUGUCUGUAGCAAGCCUUUACUGUAUUAUCUCCAAGAGACCUUUGUGUUGGGGCAUAGCACUCUGAUGGAAGAUGUAAUGCUUUCAGGGUAACUUAUUUUCUCCCUCAUCCAUGCUCUCAGAUUGCAUUACAAUUAUGUAAAAUAUGGAGUUCACCUUUACUGUCGAUGUGGAGGGUCCCCUGUGACUUCAUCAUAAGAUCCUUGCAGACUUCGGGACUGGAAAGGGGAAACCAUGUUCAGGCUGACUUUCUUUUAGAGGAACUCUGAAUCUUGUAGUUGAUUAUGUCCCUCUUUGUCUUGGUGUUUAAGAAGCUUGGACUUCAGUUUGCAUCCAGCCUAUCUUUGGGUGGCAUUUGUGUAGGAUUUGGUGGCAUGCAGGUGUUUGAGCCUUGCCUCUGACUUCAUCUUUUUUUCACACAUCCUCAUUAAAAGCAAAAUGAACCUAAUGGCUUUUUACUUAGGGUCUCAGAAAGUACAAAAUACCUUUGUAUGGUAUUUCAUAAGGCACAGUAUGAAUAUUUUUAAAAGGAGGAAAUGGGACCAGCCUAGGCAACACAGGGAGACCCCAUCUCUACAAAACAUUUUUAAAAAGGUAGCUGUAGUGGCACAUGCCUAUAGUCCUAGCUACUCAGGAGGCUGAGGUGGGAGGAUCGCUUGAGCCUGGGAGGUUGAGGCUUCAGUGAGCUAUGAUCAUGCCACUGCACUCCAGCCUGGGUGACAGAGCAAGACUGUCUUGAAAAAAAAAAGAGAGAAAAUGGGAAAUUCUAUCCUACUUUGUAAUGGAAAUGUCAUAUUUUCUCAUUUUCAUUGGGGAAAAAAUGGUGCUCUUUUGCACAGUUAACAUAUCUGUAAGAUUCCAUCAGCAUCUAUCCCAUGUUUAAAAUUCGAUUUCCUCUCUGUUCAUAGCUGGUUGUGUAAAGCCACCUUUCUCAAAUGGACAGACUCCAUUGUAGUAAGCAAAAAAGCAUUUGCAAUCUGAGAUCUAGACCUGGAUCUAGACUCCAAGAGGAGUUCCAGAUUUACUAAGGCUGACCCAAAGGGCUGAGAUCCCAUUUCUCCUUGGCCCACUUUCAUGCCUUGUCCCAAUAAUAACCUUCAGUAAAGGAGCCGCGUGGUGUUUCGACUCAGUUUUGGGGUUGGCAGAUGGGAGCAUGGGGAUGCGGGUGGUCAGUGAUCUGUGAGAUGAGGGUUCCCCAGGCUGGUUGAGACAAGUUCCUUCAGAACAAUACAGCGAACUUUUGGGACAAUGACGUUGAGGUGGAUUUCAUGCCUUCCUUGAGUCACAGUAGACUGAGGCUUGUCCUAUGGAGCGGGCUUGCUGAAGAGUUGAUGAGGAGUGAGUGUACAUUCUGAAACUACAGAAAAGUUGCAAACAGGUCAUGUGCCUUGUCGUUAUGGAAAGAUAAAUGACAGUUCUUCAGUGUUACCCAUGCUCCUGACUCAAGGGUUAUUUUGGAGGCACCUAGAGGUCCUGCUGAAGAGACAGUGCUUGACAAUCUGGAGAGUGGCAAAGAGCUGAUACCUACAAAUGCGGGAAUGAGUUUGUUAGACUCUUAAAUAUUCUAGUGGUGAGACAAAGAAAACAAAAACUUGAGGAACAUCUCUAUUUUCACCUCUUUUUACCUGUGGGGCUUCAGCUAAGAUCUCCUUUCAGCAAAAUCUCUACAGAUCUCUAAAAUUCAAGACCCGGCUGGCCUUCUUCCCAGUGAGAGAAUGUUCUCCAACAAGCUUUCUUGGAGGUCAUCUCUUCCUGCCUGUGCUUCAUUGGCACUCAAAACAUGAUAUUUUUCCAUGCCUGUUUGCUUCUAGUCCAUCUCUCAGGAAUUUCUCCAUAUAUUUCCCUGGCCUGUCCUCUGUGUGUCACUCAGAAUAAAUCAACUCUCUCUUCUAUAUGACUUCCAUCUAAAUAUUUAGAUGGGAGCUAACCUGCCUCUCCUAAACUUCCAGGUCAUAUGUAGCCACUCCUGGCUAGCCAGUUUCUCAUAAUAGGCUAUAUAUGGUUUUUCUAAUCCCUUCCCCACCUAGUUUACUCCUUCUAGAAACUGAUGUCAGCUUAUCAGUGUCCCUUCAGAAUGCAUCACUCAGAAUUGAUCAUAGUAUUGCCACAGAUGUGGUUUAACCUACCAGAGUACACUGGGAUUGGUAACUGACUUCCUUUGAUUACAAAGCUUUAGCUCCUCCUGUUUUAACCAACAGAAUCACUUGGCCAGGUAGACAAGGUAACUCUGUGUAGAAGAAGGAUUCUAAUCCUUGCUUUGUCAAAUUGACUUCUCCAGUCUAUAAAGUAUGGUGAUGAUCACUCUGGGAGGUUUUAUGGCUCACAUGAACUCCAUGCGCACCCGUUUCUUAUAAAUAAUGCUUUCCUUGGUUACCUCAUGGGGCUGUUUUGAUUUAAACAAAUAAGCAAUACUAUUUUAUGAAGAAUUGUAUAACUAUGCAGACCAAGAUAGUGUUGGCUUUUUAACUUACUCAACUCACUGAGUAAGUGUUACUAGUUCUAAAACUUUGGGGCAGGAUUUGACAUAUAUUUUGAAUAAACUGUGUAUUAACGUAAGAAAGAUCCUUCUGAUUCCCAGUUUCCUUAAUAAGUAUGCCAAGUAGUUUCCAAGUCAUUAAUGACCAAAACAGAAGAGAACACAUCUAAAUCCAAACAUUGAGGUACACAUCACCACGAGUUUCCUCUGCCAUGACAUAAUCAGCACAGUGGGCAUGGUGUUCCUUCUGACUGUACCCUCCUUCUAGGGUUACUAAACUGGACUUCAGGAGUGCGCUAGACAUAAGGAACUUUUAUGAGAAAGUAAUGCAAUUAUAUCCCUAGUGGGCCAUCUAAGAUUACCAGAUUGGCAGAUCAAGGAGAUGUGACGCCCAUAAAAGGCAGUGACAUUCAAAUGCAGAUGCCUUUCCGAAACAAGAUAGAUCUUUAAAUCUGAGGCAUUUCCCUAGGCUGGUAAUCCUGUCAGUGGGUGAAAAAUCAUGGAUUGAGUGCCCACUAUGUAUCAGGCAUGGGCAUGAGGAUUACUAAGAUGAACAGGAGCCUGACCUCCCCUCAAGGAGGGGACAUGGGCAGGUGUUCUUGGACAUGCCUUGUGUGUCCAUGCAGCCUUGGUGAUGGCUGCCCUUCUCCCUGAGUGCUUGCUUGCACACUCUCUCCCCAAGAGUCCACUCUAGGAGGGCGCCUGCCGGGCUCUUCAGCCAGUAAUAGAUCCUUGCCCUCUGGGUGGGGAUGGAGUGGGAGCAGGCUUCUCUCUAGGUUCUAGUUACUACCGUUUGCCAAGGCUUCUCUCACAGUGAGCUGCUUGAUACCCACUUUUUUGUUACUUGUUAUUUCUGAGUCUAGAUUCUUCUGGGAAUCCAGUGUCUAUACUUGUUCGCUCCUUGUUUAGAUUUGAACUUUCAAAAAUCCACUAUAAACUAUAUGUGUUCUAAGCUUUGCAGUCUAAAGGUCAUUUUCUAGACAGAGAAGACAAAAUUGACAUUCUGUUAGCUCUGCAUCUUUCUACCGUUUGUUAUACUCUUUGCUUUAGGCACUGGACCAGCUCCUCUUUAAUCAUAUAUAUAAAAUUUUUUUUUUUGAGAUGGAAUUUCACUCUUGUUGCCCAAGCUGGAGUGCAAUGGCAUGAUCUUGGCUCACUGCAACCUCCGCCUCCCAGGCUCAAGCGAUUCUCCUGCCUCAGUAGCUGGGAUUACAGGCGCUACAGAUGUGUGCCACCACGCCCAGCUAAUUUUUUUGUAGUAGAAACAGGGUUUCACCAUGUUAGCGAAGUUGAGCUCAAACUCCUGACCUCAGGUGAUCCAUCUGCCUCGGCCUCCCAAAGUGCUGGGAUUACUACAGGCAUGAGCCACUGUGCCUGGCUUAUUUAUAUUUUUUUUGAGACAGGGUCUCCCUCUGUUACUCAGGCUGGAGUGUAGUAGCACAGUCUCUGCUCACUGCAGCCUUGACCUCCCAGGCUCAAGUGAUCCUCCCACCUCAGCCUCCCAAGUUGCUGGAACCACAGGUGUGUGCCAUCAUGCCCAGCUAAUUUUUGUGGGUUUUGUAGAGACAGGGUCUCACUAUGUUGCCCAGGCUAGUCUCAAAGGACUCAAGUGAUCCUCCAGUGUUGGCCUCCCAAAUUGCUGGUGUGAGCCACUGCACCCGUCCUAGUAAUUUUUGAAGCUUUAAUUUCUUGUCAGUCUCACAAUAUUUGUAUAUUGAGUCAUAAUGUUUUUGUAUUUACCUGAUUAUAGACAUUUGGAGGGGAAAAAUUUGUGCUGGUUGGUGCCAUAUGCUGAUACCUUGAUCUGAAGACACAGUUGUACCUCUGAGAGGAGGACCUGGCUUUAAAAUGCUCCUGGACUUUACUUCUGUUUACCUGAGGCGAGCAUGAUUUUCCACAGCUUUUAAAUGUCUAGUUCCUCCGCAUCAAAUCUUUAGCACGUUCGUGCCAUGGAAUGAGUCUUAGAUUCUGUGGUGACCUCAAGAAAAGCAUGCAUUCUAUCUUGACAUCACUGUCCCAAAUGUAAAAUGUUUUUCUCUAGAAUUCCCACUCCCACCCCCCAUAAGAUACAUGCCUGAUUUUGUAAAAUAGUUCCUUUGUCCUUUUUGUCAGCAACAAUCUGAAAAAGAAUAAGAAUUCGGGAUGCAAACACAUUCUAAGCAGAGAGAAGAGCUUUAGCAAAGACAGAGAGGCAGGAACCAGCCUCAGGAAGAGUGGUAAAGGGAGUGGACAGUGGUGAAGGCUGGCAUCCCAGAUUGCUUCCAAGUAUGAUCAUCAGGCAGAAGAAGAUCUUCGCAAUUGGAUAGAAGAGGUGACAGGCAUGAGCAUUGGCCCCAACUUCCAGCUGGGCUUAAAGGAUGGCAUCAUCCUCUGCGAACUUAUAAACAAGCUACAGCCAGGCUCAGUGAAGAAGGUCAACGAGUCCUCACUGAACUGGCCUCAGUUGGAGAAUAUUGGCAACUUUAUUAAAGCUAUUCAGGCUUAUGGUAUGAAGCCACAUGACAUAUUCGAAGCAAAUGAUCUUUUUGAGAAUGGAAACAUGACCCAGGUUCAGACUACUCUGGUGGCUCUAGCAGGUCUGGCUAAAACAAAAGGAUUCCAUACAACCAUUGACAUUGGAGUUAAGUAUGCAGAAAAACAAACAAGACGUUUUGAUGAAGGAAAAUUAAAAGCUGGCCAAAGUGUAAUUGGUCUGCAGAUGGGAACCAACAAAUGUGCCAGCCAGGCAGGUAUGACAGCUUACGGGACUAGGAGGCAUCUUUAUGAUCCCAAAAUGCAAACUGACAAACCUUUUGACCAGACCACAAUUAGUCUGCAGAUGGGCACUAAUAAAGGAGCCAGCCAGGCAGGGAUGUUAGCACCAGGUACCAGAAGAGACAUCUAUGAUCAGAAGCUAACAUUACAGCCGGUGGACAACUCGACAAUUUCCCUACAGAUGGGUACCAACAAAGUUGCUUCCCAGAAAGGAAUGAGUGUGUAUGGGCUUGGGCGGCAAGUAUAUGAUCCCAAAUACUGUGCUGCUCCUACAGAACCUGUCAUUCACAACGGAAGCCAAGGAACAGGAACAAAUGGUUCGGAAAUCAGUGAUAGUGAUUAUCAGGCAGAAUACCCUGAUGAGUAUCAUGGCGAGUACCAGGAUGACUACCCCAGAGAUUACCAAUAUAGCGACCAAGGCAUUGAUUAUUAGAUCCACACAGAAGGAGCUCAGUAUUUAGUCCUUUGUUUUUAUUCAGUGAGAACCAAGCUAGCCUUGAGUAAUUUUUAUCUUGUCUUCCUAAAACACUAUUAAGCUUAUUGUACUUUUAAGAAAAAUUGCCUUACGUACAUUCCUUUUUCCUUUUUCUGCCUCUUCCCUCAAUAGUUGCCUUUUAGUGCUGUAAUAGUUAAAUCCUACAGCAUAAUCAAUAACUCGCAUAUGAAGUAAAAAGGAAUACUGUGAAAGGGGAGUACUCUUGUACAGCCAGUUCUUUUAUGCAAAAAUCUAUGCAUUUUUACAAUCUUAUAUUAAACUGGUAUUUUCAAACAAUAGGAAACUUUUUUUUUUUUUUUUUUUUUUUACAGUUUAGUGUAUCUGGUUUCUACAUGGAAGACUAAACUCAUGCUUAUUGCUAAAUGUGGUCUUUGCCAACUAAAUUUAAGAUGCAGCAUUUUAGAAAUUUACAUAUCAAUGUUUCUACAGUAUUGUUUGCUAAUUUUUAAAUAAAGUCAUGAUCAGUGUGCAUUUGUGAUUAUAUGUGUACUCAUUCUCUUACCUAGCGAACAAGAUCUUUUCAGAGUGGUGUUUCUAAAAGAGCAUGUACAAAAGUGGCCUGUGGACAUUUAGGCCUGGGUGAUGCAUUUGCUCUUCCUGUUUGUGCCAAUGUAUCAAUGUAGAGUUGCUCUGUUUUCUUCAACUGUAUUUAUUGCUGCAUUUCUCAGCAUAAACUUAUCCCAUUGUAUUUUUUAUAAAUAAAUAUUUUUUUUGAACUUUCA